GCUUUCCUCUCCGGCACCCGGCGGGCGCCCGGGCGCGGCGCCGCCGGCACCCGAGAGGCGCGGUAGCCGGCGCGGGCGGCGGGGGCCGGGCCGCGGCGGGCGCCCGGGCGGGGUCCGCGCUGAGCCGCCUUCUCGGCCGCCUGGUCCCUGCGGCGGCUGCCCGGCGGCCCGGGCGCGCGGCGCUUCGCCAUGUACACCUUCGUGGUACGCGAUGAGAACAGCAGCGUCUACGCCGAGGUCUCCCGGCUGCUCCUCGCCACCGGCCACUGGAAGAGGCUGCGGCGAGACAACCCCAGAUUCAACCUGAUGCUGGGAGAGAGGAAUCGGCUGCCCUUCGGGAGACUGGGUCACGAGCCCGGGCUGGUACAGUUGGUGAAUUACUACAGGGGUGCUGACAAACUGUGUCGCAAAGCUUCUUUAGUGAAGCUAAUCAAGACAAGCCCUGAACUGGCUGAGUCCUGCACAUGGUUCCCUGAAUCUUAUGUGAUUUAUCCAACCAAUCUCAAGACUCCAGUUGCUCCAGCACAGAAUGGAAUUCAGCCACCAAUCAGUAACUCAAGGACAGAUGAAAGAGAAUUCUUUCUCGCCUCUUAUAACAGAAAGAAAGAGGAUGGAGAGGGCAACGUUUGGAUUGCAAAGUCAUCAGCCGGUGCCAAAGGUGAAGGCAUUCUCAUCUCCUCAGAGGCUUCAGAGCUUCUCGAUUUCAUAGACAACCAGGGCCAAGUGCACGUGAUCCAGAAAUAUCUUGAGCACCCUCUGCUGCUUGAGCCAGGUCAUCGCAAGUUUGACAUCCGAAGCUGGGUCUUGGUGGAUCAUCAGUAUAAUAUCUACCUCUAUAGAGAGGGUGUGCUUCGGACUGCUUCAGAACCAUAUCAUGUUGAUAAUUUCCAAGACAAAACCUGCCAUUUGACCAAUCACUGCAUUCAAAAAGAGUAUUCAAAGAACUACGGGAAGUAUGAAGAAGGAAAUGAAAUGUUCUUCAAGGAGUUCAAUCAGUACCUAACAAGUGCUUUGAACAUUACCCUAGAAAGUAGUAUCUUACUACAAAUCAAACAUAUAAUAAGGAACUGCCUCCUGAGCGUGGAGCCUGCCAUUAGCACCAAGCACCUCCCUUACCAGAGCUUCCAGCUCUUCGGCUUUGACUUCAUGGUCGAUGAGGAGCUGAAGGUGUGGCUCAUUGAGGUCAACGGUGCCCCUGCAUGUGCUCAGAAGCUCUAUGCAGAACUGUGCCAAGGCAUCGUGGACAUAGCCAUUUCCAGUGUCUUCCCACCCCCAGAUGUGGAGCAACCUCAGACCCAGCCAGCUGCCUUCAUCAAGCUGUGACAGAGGGCACUCCCUGCUGCCUUGGAAAAAGCACGGGGUCCUGCUCCAGGGAAUGGUGAAAUGACUGGAUUGCUCUUUAUCCAGCCCACAGCAGGGGAAAGAAAGGCAACUCGCAAAGAUGAGAUGGAAGAAGGCACGUGAGCAGAGGAGGCAGCUCCCAAAGAGAGGGCUGCUCAGGGGGCUUCCCAGAUGUAGCUCUCAGCAGUGCUGUUGAGACUUUUGAAAACAACUUUGGUACACAAAGGCAGCUUUGUGAGCAGAGCUCCUUCCCCUCUCCCCGGGAACGGCAGGGCACUGGGACCUCUGGUCGGUGCCUCCCACCCACUGCAGCCCUAGUGCCUUAGCUCCAUGCCCGGCUGCAGCCCCACUGCUCUGGACUAUGGAUUGGACGUCAGAGCAUAUUGGAGGUUGCCUGUGUGUUCCCCACCCAUCCCUUCGGUAACACUCUGCCACACUAAGCUCUGUACAAGCAUGCACCAACAGUCCUUAGUUUUGUGCUGUGCACUGGCCUCUCGGCAAAGGUGGUUUCCCUCAUCACCUUCCUGAUGGUGUUUGGUCAGUCACCUGUCAGGGUUUGUGCGGGUUGGGCCCCAAAACAGCAUAUGCUGCUCUAAGUCUGCUCUCUGCAUGUUUUAGAAACAAAGUGGCAAGUCUGCCCUGAACCUGUAAGCAUCAAAUAAGCAUGAGAGAGAAAAAAACAUGAUAUAUUGCUUUACUUAAUAGGUUGAAUAUGGUAGGUCUUUGAAAAUAUGAUGAUUCAAUUUUCUCAAUUUUCUUUGCUUUAACCAAAAUUCUAAAUGCAGUUUUGCCUAGUUCCCUUUUUUUUUCUUUUUUUACUUUUUUUUAAACGUUUGUAAAAACCUCUUUGAGGAUGAGGAGUCAGUAAAAUUCCACUCCCCAAGUGGCCCUGCCCCAGACAAAGGUUGCUUUCCCCCUUUUUGUUCUUUUUAUGCCCCCAAGCACUUUCUGCAGUAGCUAGAGGGACAGGUUUCCUUCCAGGAAGGAUUCGAGUUCCUGUGCCUGUGGGUAUUAGGAGAGUAUAUAUCCUGCCUGAAUGGGGAAGUCUUCUAAAAUGGGAAAGAAGUGGUUUCAUCUCCACACAGUGUCUUGUAAAUCUCAACAAAUGUGUACUGUUAGAAGUGGCUUCCGCUUACUGGAUUAACUAAUACUUUAUAGGCUUUUCAGGAGGCCACAUCACUAGCAGUAGGGAGAACAAGAUGUCAUUUGUGUUCAGUGUAAGCUGAGUAAACAGGCCCUUCCUAGAGUGUCCUGGAAAUCACAGCAACCCAUUGAAAACUGCCCUCCCCACCAGAACGUGCUACGUUCUUUCUUCAUGCCUAUGUGUGCUCCAUUCCUCAUUUCUACUUGGCUCAAGAAAACAUUUCUGCAGUCAGGUGAGACUUUUACAAAAGAGGAGAAAAUCAAUGCCUCCUUGAACAUGAUGAGAUGUGAGAACUUACAAUGAAAAAGGCAAUAAUGAUAGAAAUUAUUUCUUAGGUACAGCAAUAGUUGAUAGGAUGUGAGGGUGUUACCUUGGGGUGAAGUGGAGAAGGUCCCAGGUGAAUUGGCUCUCAUGGAAAUUUGGAAUUACAAAAUAAACGUCCUGGGGGUUACCCAGAAUACAGAUUUAAAAGUUUGCCUGUAGAGCAAAAUAAAACAGUCAGUUGUAGUCAUUAAUCCUUGAGGCCCAACGCAGCCGAUGGGUUGGUGUUUGGGAAAUUCUGAGAUGGGAGUGAGAUCUGAUCGGAUCCUGGGAAGAUGUAUACCCAGUUAGAACGUGUAGGGUUCUGGGUCCCUGGCAAGUCUAGGUGGGCGGGUGACAGGGAAAGCAUGGGCAUUUUUGUAUUGCUGUCACAUGCUAACAGAGGUUUGUAAUUAUCUUUUGGACCCAAAUUAUAGAGACAUUCACGAGUUUUCUAGCCCUCACAGUAACAGAGCUAAGAAUUCAGAUGUCAGGAAGUCUGUGAAUCUUGAUGGAUUUUCUGAGAAACCUGACUCAAUGGCAUAUAUAAGAGGGAAGUAAGACUUUUAAGAAAAGAAAAAGUUAUGCCUCAUUCCUCAUGUGGCUUCCAAUAAGUAUCUUAGGAACUUAUUUCCUUUUUAAAAAAUAUUUUUUAAAUUUUUAAAAUUUGAUUUUAAAUUUCAAAUAAAUUUAAAUAAAUUUUAAAUAAAUUUUAAAUAAAAUUUUACAGAGACGUGGUCUCACUGUGUUGCCCAGGCUGGAUUGCAGUGGCUAUUCGCAGUUGUAAUCAUAGCACACUGCAGCCUCGAAUUUCUGGGCUUGAGCAGUCCUCCCGUCUCAGCCUCCUGAGUAGCUGAGACUACAGGUGCACACCACCAAGCCUGGCUUUAUGUAUUUAUUUCUGUUCAUGCGGAAUGAUUGGUUCAGAACUGUUCCUUUCCCUUCCAUGAUGUCCUUGACACAGAAGGUUAUGCCUGGCUCCCAGUCAGGCUUCAUACUUUUGGUCCAUGUAAGUGCUACCCGUUGCUGGGGGAGGAGUCAUGGUUUAUUUGGAAAUGUCAGUUGCAAUCAUGGUUCUGUCAUUUGACUGCACAGUAUCAGAGGAGCCUGUUAACCUCUCUGUGCCUUAGUUUCUUAGCCCAUGAAAGAGAUCAUUGCCUGACCCAGGGACUACCUCAAGGGCUUUUGAUGAGGACAAGUGACAGUAGGAAGAUGCAAGAGCCUUUAGUACCAAGGUUCUCAACACUGACUACAUGCUGGAAUGACUGUGAAGCUUUUAAAAAAUGUUAGUGCCCACUCUUCCCCUGUACCCCCGGACAGUUAAAUCAGAACCUCAGACAGCAAUAUGCCUUGAGAUGCCUUGAACCAUGCUUGAGAAGGAAGGACAAACACAUUAUUAUCUUGGAAGAAUUGCAUAAGGCUUAUGACUUAAAAAAAAAAAUUCUUUUUGGAAACACAAGCAUUUCUUUAAGGAUGACCGGAUGUUGCCGUAUGUAUUUAUGGCACAAGCAGGUGUUGUCUAAGCAGUUUCUCUGUUUGCUUGUCAUAGCAGCAUUUGGAAACUCAAACAUGCUUUCAUUUACAUAAAUAGUUUAUGAAGCUUUGACAACAAAUGUAAACAGACACGAAAUUAUAAAUCUGCUAAAUAUGUAUUAAGGGUAUUAAUUAUUGAAAGUCCCUUUCCCCAAAACUCAACUCCUAUGGCAAUUAUGAACUCCAUUUUACCAAGAACAUUUAAGUGCCUCAGCAUCUGUAUGAUAUAGUGGAGCAGGUGCUGACAUAGGUACCAGCUGACAUGAUGUGUCACUAGCUCUGUGGGAUGAUUGCCACAUACAUGGAACACCUGGGAGUGCUGGAAAUGUACUGUGAUCGAAGUGACAAAGUGUGUUUUCAUUCACAGUGGAGGCUACAUCAAGCAAGGGGAGGUCCAGCCCUCUUGCAAGUGUGGUGAGAGGCUCUACUAGCAAAGACAUGGGCACCGGAGUAGGUCCCGUGUAGCAUGCGGGUGCUGUAGAGAAAAUUCAGUGACGUACAUGGCUCUGGUUCUGGACACAAAAUCUGUACUGGAGAGGAAAUGACUGCUGAAAUAAGGCGAUUGUAUGAAUAUUUAAAAUGCCUGGAACACUAAAGUAAAGUAAUGAUAUUUCAAGUGUUUUUGUGCUCUUUGGUUCUUGUUGUAGGUAUUGACUGUCCUGGGAUAUCACUGGUCAUUUAAAUUCACCAUAUAAUUAGCCGGGCAUGGUGGCAUGUGGUGGUGGCUGAGGUGGGAGGAUCGCUUGAGGCUGAGGUGUGAGGCUGCAGUGAACCAUGUUCACACCACUGUACUCUAGCUUGAGCAACAGAGCAAGACCCUGUCUCAAAAGUAAAUAAAUAAUAAAGUAAAUAUAAAUCCAUGAUGCCGUUACUCAGGGGUAGACAGACUUUCUGUAAAAGGCCAGAUAAUAAAUCUGCUAGGCUUUGCAAACCAUGUAGGGCCUUUUUUGCAUACUUUUUGUUUUUUUCUCCAACUCUUAGCUCAUAGGCCGUAUAAAAGCAGGCCAGAUGUGCAGUAAUUUGCUGACCCCAGGAUGUUACCCAAUACAUAAGCCAACAGAUUGUCCUUCAAAACUGAUGAGCUUCUCAGUGAAGCACUGAGACUAUUUCAGCUGCCAAAGUCCCAGCCCAUCGUUUCUUACGUGUCUUGUGUAUCGAGUUCUUGUAAAGCAUUUCACCAAGGCCAGGUUUUUAAAUACCUAUAAACCUCACACACCUGAGAUGCUUAGUCUUGUGGAUAGAAAGAGUUUCAUUAAUGCAAAUUGUUAUUAACUUGUAACUUCUUGUGCAAUAAGGCUGAAUGCUUUGGACAUCUUUCCUUUGUAUGGCUGGCCUGCCUUCUGUGGCUGCUUCCACUUCAUAAAUAUACCUCUGGCACAGAGGAGGUUUCCAUGCCAGAAGCCCUGUGUAGGCACUCCACUCCAAACAGGUUUCACAUACACUAUGACACAUUCCCAGUGGACUCAGCAGAGAUUGCAUGGGCAGGGUGCAGGGUGCAGGGUGCAAGCAGACAUGGAUCCAGGCAGGCACCUACUUAGGACCCUGAGAGUGGACAGGCCCAAAGCCUUUGGAAGACUUCUCUUAAAGACUGGUCCCACUUCCUGUCAGUAGCUACACCUCCUUCUUAACCUGAAGUUCUCCCAUAACCCAUAUUUUAGAAGUGUUUUCCCCAAAGCAUCCCUCCAUAUCUUAGUCUAUUUUGUAUUGCCAUAACAGAAUGUUACAGAGAAGUGUAUGUGGCUCACGGUUCUGGAGGAUGAGAAGUCCAAUAUCAAGGGGCUAUAUCUGGUGAGGGCCUUCUUGCUGCCUCAGCAUGGCAGAAGGCAUCACAUGGCAAGAGAGGAAUGGAGUCUAACUCACCCUUUAACUAGCAACCCAUUCCUGUGAUAACUAACCCACUCCUGGCAUAACAUCAUUAAUUUAUUCAUGAGGGUAGAGCUCUCGUGACCUAACCUCUUACAGGUCCCACCUCUCAACACUAUUGCAGUAGAGAUUAAGUUUCCAACACAUUUACUUUGGGGAACACAUUCAAACCAUAGCAGUCCCUGAAGGCAAAGGAAAAUGAACCCCUCUCCAAUGCAAUACAUAGUAGCAGAACUUGAAGAUUGUUGCAAGCAUAAUUCCUUUCAAAAAUUAUGAGAGGACAUCAGUGGGCAUAAUAGAGUAACAACCUCUGAAAACCCUCUCUUCCAUAAAAGCAAUGAGAACACUAGCAAAACUGUCUAGACAUUAACCAGAGGCUUGCAGCAAUCCAUUUAUUCAAGAAAAGGCCUGUAAUCCCAGCACUUCGGGAGGCCAAGGCGGGCGAUCACGAGGUCAGGAGAUGGAGACCAUCCUGGCUAACACAGUGAAACCCCAUCUCUACUAAAAAUACAAAAAAUUAGCCGGGCGCGGUGGCAGGUGCCUGUAGUCCCAGCUACUUGGGAGGCUGAGGCAGGAGAAUGGCGUGAACCUAGGAGGCAGAGCUUGCAGUGAGCCGAGAUCACGCCACUGCACUCCAUCCAGCCUGGGUGACAGUGCGAGACUCUGUCUCAAAAAAAAAAAAAAAAAAAAAAGGAAAGGGUUGCAUCUGGGUAAGAAAAGCAAGCUUUCUGACAUUUUAAUGUACCCUAUUCCCACUCCCCCUUUCCCCAGCUCCACAACAGCCUCGGCCACACAAUCAUGCUGACAUCCAGCAGCAGAGCAGCCACCGUAGGGCUCAGAAGGGGAUUGGAACUCCUCCAAAGCUUCAUUACCAGAGAAUUGCCAUUUGGCCUUUUUGGUAGUUCCAUGUAAGUCCCUACUCCUAGGUCUUGUCUUUAUUUGAUGUGACUAAGAGGUUACCCAGUGUGAACAACCUUUUCCCUGGGUGCAUUUGUCAAAAAAAAUCAACAGCAAUUGUUGAACAUCUCAGCUUCCUAAGGUGGCUGUAACAGUUGGAACAAACAAACUGACCAAAAGACUUAGAAGGAAAAACUGGGAAUGAGAUUUCUAUAGGACGUUUUGAAAAGCUUCAACCUAUUCCUAAGAAUGCAGAAGGCCACACACAUGUGUAGGACUGUGCACAUGCCCAGAAGAGACCUGAGAAUUCCCCAGCUCUUUCGUCUGACCUUAAGUGUCUGCACAAACAGAGAGGACAGAGGCAGAAGGAGGGAAAGAGGGAGGGAGGAAAGGUAGGAAGGGGAGAAAGAGAGAGGAAGAAAGAGAAAGGAAAGAAAGGCAGGCAGAAAGAAGGAGAAAGGGAGGGAGGGAGGGAAAGGAGGGAGGGAAGAAAAGAGAAAGAUUGAGAAAGAAAAAAGAGAAAGAAGAAAGAAAAGAAAAAAGGAAAGAAAGUUAGUUUAUAAAAUAGAACCAAGUAGAAAUUUUAGAGUUGCAAAGUACAAAAAUGCAAAUGAAAGAUUUACUUGAGAAGUUUAAAAAAUGUGUGAACUGGUAAAAGAAGUAAUCAGCAAAUUAGAAGUCAUUUGAGAUUAUCCAGUCUGUGGAACAGAAAAAAAAAAUCAGCAAAGAAAAAUGAUCAGUGCUUCAGACACCCGUCAGACACCAUCAAACAUACCAACAUACACAUAAUAGGAGUCCUAGAAUAGAUAAGUGAGAGAGAGGGAAGGGGAUAAAACAUAUACUGGAAGAAAUAGUGGCCAAAACCUUUCCCACUUUGAGGAAAAACAUUAAAGUGAAUCCAAGAAGCUCAACAAAUUCUAAGCAGGAAAGACUCAAAGAGUCCACCUCAAGACACACCAGCCACUAAGUAAAUAAUUUUAAAUAUAUAGUAAAAAAUGACAAGGAAACAGAAAUGUUACACUAGAAAAUAUAUAAGAAAAGAGAAGGAAGUAAUGAAAAAUAGAGGAGAAAAAAAAGGCAAGAGGCCUAAAGAAACCAACAGUAAAAUGGUAGAUAAAUCCUGCCUUAUCAGUAAUUUCAUUAAAUGCAAAUGAAUUAAAUACUCCAAUCAGAAGGUAGAGAUUGGCAAAUUGAUUUUUUUUAAAAAUCAUGAUCCAACUAUAUGCUAUCUACAAAAAACACACUUCAUUUUAUUUUUAUUUUUAUUAUUUAGAGACAGAGUCUUGCUCUGUUGCCUAGGUUGGAGUCUAGUGGUGUAAUGAUAGCUCACUGCAGCCUCAAACUUCUGGUUUCAAGUAAUCUUCCCACCUUAGCCACCCAAGUAGCUGGAACUAUAGGUGCCUGCCACCAUACUUGGCUAAUUUAAAACAAUUUUUUUAGAGAUAGGACCUGGCUUACUUCAAAACUUACCUGGCUAAUUUCACUUCACAUAACGAUCUUCAGUUCCAUCCAUGUUGUUGGAAGUGACAGGAUCUCACUCUUUAUGGCUGAACAGUACUCCAUUGUGUAUAAGCAAUAUAUUUUCUUUAUCCAUUCAUCUGCUGAUGGACACUUAGGUCGCUUCCAAAUCUUGGCUAUUGCAAACAAGGCUGCAGUAAACAUGGGAGUGCAGAUAUCUCUCCAAAAAAAAUUUUUUUUUUUUUAGAGAUAGGGUCGUACUGUGUUUCCCAAGCUGGUCUUGAACUCCCGUCCUCAGGCAAUCCUCCUGCCUCAGUCUCCCCUAAGCAGCUGGGAUUACAGGCAUCAGCCAAUGCACCUGGCAAAACACACUUUAGAUUCAAAAACACAAACAGGUUGAAAGUAAAAUGAUGGAAAAAGAUAUACCAUGCAAACAGUAACUCAAAGAGAAGUGGAGUAGCUAUACUAAUGUUAGACAACAUAAACUUUAAGAAAAAAAUUGUUUCUAUAGACAAAGAAGGACUUUUUUUUAAUAGUUCCAACUUUUAUUUUAAAUUCUGGAGGUACAUACACAGGUUUGUUACAUGGGUCCUGAGGUUGGGGUACAGAUCCCAUUACCCAAGUAGUAAGCAUAGUACCUAAUGGUUAGCUUUCCAAUCCUUGCACCCCUCCCUCCCUUCUCCCUCUUGUCAUCUUUAGUGUCUCUUGUUGCCAUUUUUGUGUCCAUGUGUAUCUAAUGUUUGGCUCCCACUUAUGAGACUGUGCAAUAUUUGGUUUUCUGUUCCUGUGUUAUUUCACUUAGGAUAAUGGCCUCCAGCAGCAUCCAUGUUACUGCAAAGGACAUGAUUUCAUUCUUUUUUAUGGCUGCAUAGUAUUCCAUGGUAUAUAUGUACUAUAUUUUCUUUAUCCAAUCCACUGUUGAUGGGCACCUAGGUUGAUUCCAUGUCUUUGCUCUUGUGAAUAGCACUGUGAUAAACAUAUAGGUGCAUGUGUCUUUCUGGUAGAAUGAAUUGUUUUCUUUUGGAUAUAUACCCAGUAAUGGGAGGCUAUGUUGAAUGGUAGCUCUGUUUUUGUUUGUUUGUUUGUUUGUUUGGUGGAGUCUCUCUCUGUCACCCAGGCUGGAGUGCAGUGGUGUGAUCUGUGCUCACUGCAACCUCCGCCUCCUGGGUUUAAGCGAUUCUCCUGCCUCAGCCUCCCAAGUAGCUGGGACUACAGGCGUGUGCCGCCAUGCCCAGCUAAUUUCUGUAUUUUUAGCAGAGACAGGGUUUCACCAUGUUGGCUAGGCUGGUCUUGAACUCCUGACCUCAGGUGAUCGACCUGCCUCAGCCUCCCAAAGUGCUGGGAUUACAGGCAUGAGCCACCAUGCCCAGCUGCUCUGUUUUAAAUUCUUUGAGAAAUCUCCAAACUUCUUUCCACAGUGGUUCAACCAAUUUACAUUCCUGCCAGCAGUGUAUAAGCAUUCUCUUUUUUUCCUUAGCCUCUUCAGCAUCUGUUAUUUUUUGACUUUUUAAUAUAGCUAUUCUGACUGGCGUGAGAUGAUAUCUUAUUGUGGUUGUGAUUUCCAUUUCUCUGUUGAUUAGUGAUGAUGAACAUUGUCUCAUAUGUUUCUUGGCCACUUGUAUGCCAAGGACAUUUUAUAUUGAUAAAAGGGUCAGUCCAUUAGGAAAAUAUGACAAUUAUAAACAUAUGUACCUAGCAAUACAGCCUAAAGAUACAUGACAUAAAAACUUAGAGAAUUGAAGGAAGAAACAGACAAUUUAACUACAAUAGUUGGAACCCUCAAAACUCCAUUUCAAUAAUAGCUAGAGCAACUAGGCAGAAGAUCAACAAGAAAAUAGAAAACACUAUAAACCAACUAGACUUGACAAAUAUCUACAAGGCACUCCACCCAACAGCAGCAAAAUACACAUCCUUCUCAAGUGCACAUGGAACAUUCUCUGGGGUAGAUCACAUGCUAGGCCAUAAAACAAGUCUCAGUAAAUUUAAAAGAAUUGAAAUUAUACUACAUAUGUUCUCUGACCAUGUUGGAAUAAAAUCAGAAAUCAGUAACAAAUUUUGUUAAUUUCUGUAUUAAUGAAGAAAUAUACAAGUAAAGAGGUUGGACUAAUAAUAAUUCUUUUAAAACUUCCCACAGGGAAAAGCCCAGGACCAGAUUGUAAGCCAGAUGGUAAGGAAUUAACACCAAUAUUUCAUAGAGUCUCCUAAAAAAUAGAAGAGAAGAAAAUACUCCUCAAUUGAGAAGAGUGUCCUCAACUUUAUGAGGUCACUCUUAAUACCCUGAUACCAAAACCAGACAAAGAUGUCACAAGAAAAGCAAAUAGCAGACCAAUAAUCUCUUGGGAAUACAAACGGAAAAAAUCUUCAACAAAAUACUAGUAAACCAAAUCCAGCAACAUAGAAAAAGGAUUAUACAUUAUGACUAAGUGGGACUUAUCCUAAGAUUACAAAGUUUGGAAUAACUCAUGUUCUCUUGUAAGUGGAAGCUAGGCUGAGCACGGUGGCUCACUCCUAUAAUCUCAGCACUUUUAGGAGGCCAAGGUGGGCAGAUCAAAUGAGGCCAGGAGUUUGAGUCCAGCCUGGGCAACAUGAUUAAAUCUGGUCUCUAUAAAAAAUACAAGAAUUAGCCAGGCAUGGUGGUGCAUGCCUGUAAUCCCAGCUACUCUGAUGGCUGAGGCACAAGAAUCGCUUGAACCUGAGAAGAGGAGGUUGCAGUGAGCAGAGAUCGCACAACUGCUCUCUGUCCUAGGUGACAGAGCAAGUCCUGUCUCAAAAAAAUUAAAAAGUGGGAGCUAAACAUUGGGUACACAUGGACAUAAAGUUGGGAAGAGGCCAGUCGCGGUGGCUCACGCCUGUCAUCCCAGCACUUUGGGAGGCCAAGGCGGGCGGAUCAUGAGGUCCGGAGAUCAAGACCAUCCUGGCUAAUAUGGUGAAACCCCGUCUCCACUAAAAAUACAAAAAAUUAGCCGGGCGUGGUAGCAGGCGCCUGUAAUCCCAGCUACUCAGGAGGCUGAAGCAGGGGAAUCACUUGAACCUGGAAGGCGGAGGUUGCAGUGAGCCGAGAUUGCGCCACUGCACUCCAGCCUGGGUGACAGAGACUCUGUCUAAAAAAAAAAAAAAAAAAAAAAAAGAUGGGAACAGCAGACACUGGGGACUACUAGAGCCAGGAGAGAAGGAGGGGAGCAAAGAUUGAAAACUACCUAUUGGAUACUGUGCUCGCUACCUGGGUGACAGGUUCAACCAUACCCCAGACCUCAGCAUCACCCAAUAUACCUUUGUAACAAAUUCGCACAUGUACCCCCCUGAUUCUAAAAUAAACGUUGAGAAGGGGAAAAGAAAGAAUGCAAGGUUUUUUUAACAUACAAAAUUUACUUAAUAUAAUAUACCACUUUAAUAGAAAAAAGAGGACAAAAAGCACAUGAUCAUUUCAAUAUACACUGAAAAAGCAUUUGGCAAUACACAACACUCUUUCUUGGAAAAAACCUUUCAACAAACUAGAAAUAAAUUACUUCCUCAACAUGAUAAAGAGCAUCUUUGGAAAAACCCACAGCCUACAUCAUAUUAAUGGUGAUGUGAAAGCUCCAGUUGGGAGCUUUCUUCCCAAUAUCAGGCACAAAACAAGUAUAUUUAUUCUUGUCACUUCAACAUUGUAUUAAAUGUUCUAGACAGAGCAAUUCGACAAAAGGAAGGAAAGAAGACUGCGCAUUCAGAUUGGAAAGGGAGAAGUAUGAUGAUCUCUCUUUGCAGACGACAAGAUACCAUAUAGAAAAAGUCCUAAGAAAUCCACUUACGCUGUUAGAACUAAUAAAGAGUUUAGCAAGAUUGCCAGACACAAGAUCAAUAUACAAAACUCAAUGGUAUUUCUACAUAUUACAAACAAUUUGAAGUUAAGAAAACAAUUCCAUUUAUAUCAACACCAAAAAGAAUGAAAUACUUAGGAAUAAAUUUAACAAAAGUUCAUUUCUACACCAAAUACUACAAAACAUCUCUGAAAGAAAUUAAAGAACACCUAAAUAAAUGGAAAGACAUCCCAUGUUUAUGGAUUGGGAGAUAAUUAUUGUUAGGAUGAAAAUAGGCCCCAAAUUGAUCUACCAAUUGAACACAAUCCUGAUCAAGAAUCUCAGCCUUCUUUGCAGAAAUUGACAAGCUGGGCCGGGUGUGGUGGCUCACACCUGUAAUCCCAGCACUUUGGGCGGCCAAGGCAGAUGGAUUACUUGAGGUCAGGAAUUCAAGACCAGCUUGGCCAACAUGGUAAAACCCUGUCUCUAUUAAAAAUACAAAAUUAGCCAGGCAUGGUGGUGCAUGCCUGUAAUCUCAGCUAUUUGGGAGGCUGAGGCAGGAGGUAGAGGUUGCAGUGAGCCAAGAUCAUGCCACUGCACUCCAUCCUCAGCAACAAGAGCAAAACUCUGUCUCAAAAAAACAAAAAACAAAAAAAAAAAAAAAAGAGAAAGAAAUUGACAAGCUAAGCUGACGCUAAAAUCCAUAUUGAAAUACAAAGGAUCAAAUAAAUCUGGAGAAAGAAGAACAAAGUUGGAGGAUGUGCACUUCCUGAUUUCAAAAUUUAUUACAAAGCUGUAUUAAUCAAAUCUGUGUAGUUUGUAGACAGAUAUACAGAUAAAUGUAGAUAGACAUACAGAUCAAGAGAAUAGAACUGAGAGUCAAAAAUAAACCCUUGCAUCUAUAGUGAACUGAUUUUCGACAAGGAGGCCAAGACAAUUUGAUGAGGGAAAGAAUAGUCUUUUUAACAAAUGGUGUUAGGACAACUGGAUAUCCACAUGCAAAGGAAUAAAGUGAUAUGCCUUUCUCACACCAUAUACAAAAAUUAGCUCAGAAUGAGUCAAAGACUUAAAUGUAAGAGUUGAAACUACAAAACUCUUAGUAGAAAAUAUAGGUGAAAAUCCCCAUGAUUGAAAAAUAUCUAGUAUUUGAUAGCACAACAGGGUGACUGCAGUCAGCAAUAAUUUGUUGUACCUUCAAAAAUAACUGAGGAAGUACAAUUGGAAUGUUCAUGACAGAAAUGAUGAAUGCUUGAGGUGAUGGAAACCCCAUCUACCCUCCUGUGAUGAUUACAUCGUAUGCCUAUAUGAAAACAUCUCAUAUACCUCAUAAAUAUGCUAAUUAUGUACCCAUAAAUUUUUUUUUAAAUCCUCAUGACCUUGGAUUACACAAUGAUGUCUUAGAUAUGAUAUAAAAAGACAGGCAACAAAAGAAAAAAACUACACUUCAAAAUUAAAACGUUUUGCUUCAAAGGACACCAGCAAGAAAGUAAAAACCCACAGAAUGGGAGAAAAAUAUUUGCAAAUCAUGGAUCUGACAAGGACUAGUAUAGGCUAUAUAAAGAACUACAACUACUCAGUUGGCCGGGCGCGCGCGGUGGCUCAUGCCUGUAAUCCCAGCAUUUAGGGAGGCAAGGCGAGAGGAUCACUAGAGGCCGGAAGUUCAAGACCAGCCUGUGCAACAGACUCCCGGCUCGAAUUUUUUAUAAAAAGUGAUAUAGGAAUGAAAAGUACCAGCUGAACUAGGAAAGGGGAAGUUGACAGUAAGGAGGGACUAUCAGGGGCAGGAGGAUACUGGGUAGUGGUGGUUUAAUUCAUUGUUUUAAUUGUGGUGAUGGCUGCAUGGUUGUAUACAUAGGUCAAAACUUAACGCGUACACUUUAAAUGUGUGGUUUAUUGUAUGCCAGUUAUAACGCAAUAUAGCUGUUAAACACAAACACAAUAAAGUUGAAAAACCA